GUACGCCAUCAGCCGGCGCCGCGCCGCCGGGUGUUACUUUGCCCCGCCGGCGGGGCGGUCAGCCUCCUGUCACCGCCUGUUCCGGCUAUGGUCCCGUCCGGUGUUCUGUAAGUUGGCAACCUAGGCUCCUGACGCGACCCUGGUCCUGAUGGCGGCGGCGACGGCCGCGGCAGCCCUGGCGGCGGCCGAUCCCCCUCCCGCAAUGCCGCAGGCGGCAGGGGCCGGAGGGCCCACAACCCGCAGAGACUUCUACUGGCUGCGCUCCUUUCUGGCCGGAGAAGAAGAGGAGUUUACUUCAAACAGAACCUGGCAAUCGGAUAAAUACCUUCAAGUGUCUGUCUCCGUAAAAAUGUUCCAGAAGAAGAGGAGGUUACUUCAAACAGAACCUGGCAGUUGGAUUAAUACCUUGAAGUGUCUGUCUCCAUAACCACAUUUUAGCAAGAUUCCCAGCCUUCCUCAGGUAUUGCUGGAUGCUGUGCCAAAACAACAGUUGCUCCAUUGGAUCGAGUAAAGGUUUUAUUACAAGCUCACAAUCACCAUUACAAGCAUUUAGGAGUAUUUUCUGCAUUGCGUGCUGUUCCUCAAAAAGAAGGAUUCCUUGGAUUGUAUAAAGGAAAUGGUGCAAUGAUGAUUCGAAUCUUUCCCUAUGGUGCAAUCCAGUUUAUGGCAUUUGAGCAUUAUAAAACGUUAAUUACUACGAAGCUGGGAAUUUCAGGUCAUGUGCACAGAUUAAUGGCUGGAUCCAUGGCAGGUAUGACAGCAGUUAUCUGUACUUACCCUCUUGACAUGGUUAGGGUCCGCCUAGCAUUCCAGGUGAAAGGGGAACACAGCUAUACAGGAAUUAUUCAUGCUUUCAAAACAAUUUAUGCAAAGGAAGGUGGUUUCUUUGGAUUUUACAGAGGUCUGAUGCCUACUAUUUUAGGAAUGGCUCCAUAUGCAGGUGUUUCAUUUUUUACUUUUGGUACCUUGAAGAGUGUUGGGCUUUCCCAUGCUCCUACCCUUCUUGGCAGACCUUCAUCAGACAAUCCUAAUGUCUUAGUUUUGAAAACUCAUGUAAACUUACUUUGUGGUGGUGUUGCUGGAGCAAUAGCGCAGACAAUAUCCUACCCAUUUGAUGUGACUCGUCGGCGAAUGCAAUUAGGAACUGUUCUGCCGGAAUUUGAAAAGUGCCUUACCAUGCGGGAUACUAUGAAGUAUGUCUAUGGACACCAUGGAAUUCGAAAAGGACUCUAUCGUGGUUUAUCUCUUAAUUACAUUCGCUGUAUUCCCUCUCAAGCAGUGGCUUUUACAACAUACGAACUUAUGAAGCAGUUUUUUCACCUCAACUAAAAAAAAAUUAUGGUUGGUUUUUCUUAAUACAUUCUCAGAGGGAGAAAUGAAACAUUACUAUAAUUGUGGGGGGAACAUUACUUGAAUGGGGAUAUUUACCCUGUCACAAGAGCCACUGGUAUUUUAGUACUUGAUUAUUUUUUCUUUAGUCACAAAUCAGAACUGCUUACCAUACUUUUUGAUGCCAAACAUUAUACCUUAGAACAUUGAAGAAAAUAUUCCUAAGCUGAUGCUGGCUAAACCGCUUUAAAGUUUUAUUUGGAAGUAGAACUAGCUUUAAAACGGGGUUCAAGAGGUUGCCAUUAGCUUUGUCAUGCUGUUCAAAGUUUUUAAUUGUUAUCAUGGUUUUUAAAAGACUGACAGUGUUUAUUAUUAUUAAAAUAAACAGGGUUGGUUAUAUUGCAAUAGAAUAAUGAGAAUUGAAUUUUUAAGUUCUAUGAAACAGCCAGCAUUGACAUUUUAUUUUUGUUAUCUCUCUUCUCACAAUUAUGCUCCACUGGAUAAUAGGAAAAACACUUCUUUCCUUCAUUUUUUAAAUAAAAUUAAUGUUGUAUUUAAAAGGUAGCCAUGUAGAGACACAAAAAUAAAUGAAGAAGCUGGACAUGGUGGGAUGGGCAUGUGGUCCCAGCUACUCUGGAAGCUGAGGUGAGAGGAUCACUUGAGCCCUGGAAUUCCAUGCCAGCCUAUGCAACAUCAUGAAACCCCACUUAAUAAAUGAAUGAACGACUAAGUCUUGCUCAAAUGUUAUUAUGAGGUACUAUGAGUGACUUACAUGUGUUUUAAAAUGUCAGUGUGUUUCCCAGAGGCAGAAAUAAAAAUACUGAAUAUCUUUGCUCUUAAAAAAAAAGUAACACUAUAGAUUUGUUUUUGUUAGAUGAUUUGCUCUAUAGUAGAAUAUUUAAGUAGACUGUGAAAUAUUUAUUAAUAUAGAUGUGAAUAUCAAAAAAUGUUUCUAAGGUAUUAUGAUGCAUCAACUAGUUCUUCCAUGUAAAAUAAUUUUAGUGCAAUAUGAAGACGUAGAAAUGUAAAAUAUGAUUUGAAUUGUUAUCCUUUAUAUUAAGAAAAUGUUUUAAAAUGUAAGAAUUCCAUUUAUUCUGUUUAGAGUACUUUUUAUGAUUUAUUAUAAGCGUGUCAUAAAUGGGAAGGGAAUAUUUAAAGUUCUGUGUUCAGAAAGAGUAAUUUGUAGAACUGAUGUGACUUUUUUUUUUUUUUUGAGAUGGAGUCUCGCUCUAUCGCCCAGGCUGGAGUGCAGUGGCGCGAUCUCAGCUCACUGCAACCUCUGCCUCCCGGGUUCAAGUGAUUCUCCUGCCUCAGUCUCCCGAGUAGCUGGGACUACAGGUGCCCACCACCAAAAAUUCGCCUGGCUAAUUUUUGUAUUUUUAGUAGAGACGGGAUUUCACCGUGUUAGCCAGGAUGGCCUCGAUCUCCUGAACCUCAUGAUCUGCCCACCUUGGUCUCCCAAAGUGCUGAGAUUACUGGCGUGAGCCACGGCGCCCGGCCCUUUGAUGUGACUUUAAAGACAUUAGAAGGCCAGGUGUGGUGGCUCACGCCUUUAUUCCCAGCACUUUGGGAGGCCGAGUUGGGUGGAUCACCUGAAGUCAGGAGUUUAAGAUCAGCAUGGUGAAACCCCACCUCUACUAAAAAUACAAAAAGUAGCAGGUGUGGUGGCUCGUGCCUGUAGUCCCAGUUACUCGCGAGGCUGAGACAUGAGAAUUGCUUGAGCUCGGGAAGCGGAGGUUGCAGUGAGCUGAGAUCACACCACUGCACUCCAGCCUGGGUGACAGAAUGAGCCUCCAUCUCAAAAAAAAGGAGACAUUAGAAAACUAAGUUGAGUCCAGGCGUGGUGGCUCUUGCCUGUAACCCUAGCACUUUGGGAGGCUGAGGCGGGAGGAUAUCUUGACCCCAGGAGUUCGAGACCAGCCUGGGCAACAUAGUGAGACCCCGUUUCUUUCAAACAAAAGAAGGAAAACUAAGUUGAAAGUGUUAUUUUUGCUUCAAUUUUUAUUUCUUUACAUAAAAGGUUUCUUGUCAUACCUUGGUAAAAAUUUGAUGAGCUGGUUUCAUUUUGAAAGCCUUUAUUUUAAAAAUAAGUAUGUAUCUUUGUAUGAUUUAUAAGUGUACCAGUAGGUAGAAAUACAUGUGUUCUUGGCCAGAUGUGGUGGCUCACGCCUGUAAUCCCAGCAUUUUGGGAGGCUAAGGCGAGUGGAUCACCUGAGGUCAGGAGUUCAAGACCAGACUGGCCAACGUGGAGAAACCCUGUCUCUACUAAAAAUACAAAAAUCAGCCGGGCAUGGUGGCGGGCGCCUGUAAUCCCAGCUACUUGGGAGGCUAAGGCAGGGAGAAUUGCUUGAACCCAGGAGGCACAGGUUGCAGUGAGCCAAGAUUGCGCCAUUGCACUCCAGCCUGGGUGGCUGUAUAAAAGCCUGUAUAAAAAUUUCUUUUAUACAGAGUGAGACUGUAUAAAAGAAAAAAAAAGGCUGUACAAAAAUUUCUUUUAUACAGAGACUGUAUAAAAGAAAAAAAAAAGAAAUACAUGUGUUCUUAAAACCAUUUGUAUAUUUUCAUUUCUAGACCACACUGUAGCUAAUUAUUGUUAUUAAAUGUUAAGAUAAUUUAAGUAUAUAAAAUAAGUAUUGAGCCGGGCAUGGUGGCUCACCCCUGUAAUCUCAGCACUUUGGGAGGCUGAGGCGGGGGGAUCACGAGGUCAGGAAAUCGAGACCAUUGUGGCUAACACGGUGAAAACCUAUCUCUACUAAAAAUACAAAAAAUUAGCUGGGCGUGGUGGCACGCACCUGUAGUCCCAGUUACUCAGGAGGCUGAGACAGGAGAAUCACUUGAACCUGGGAGGCGGAGCUUGCAGUGAGCCGAGAUCGUGCCACUGCAUUCUAACCUGGGCGACAGAGCAAGACUCCAUCUCAAAAAAAAAAAAAAAAAAAAAAAAGAUACCUCAGUUAGGUUAUCAGUAAAAGGGGAUUGCAAAUAUCUUUUAAAUAAAAAUUUGCAUUCUAUAUGUUAUAGAAUACAGAGGAUAUUAAAAAUAAAUUUUAUCCAUGUUUUGACAAUUUCUUUCUUUCAACUGUUUACAUAUUGAAGCACAAAUGCUAAACAUAAGUCAGAAUGGAAGAAUAUUUAAAAUAAUGACUGUGUUUAUAUCUGAUUUAUUUCAGAUUGCCCAAAGUGCAUCUUGCCAGGUUAUCUUCCAUUUGAAGACUGACAUUUUAUUUCUUUUUUGAUCUUUAUUGUUCCUCUCUUCCACCUCUCAGUGGGUAUAGCUCUCUGGUCUGUAGAAUGGGACAGUGGUCUGGUUUCCAGAUUGAUAAGUGAGGUAUACCUCCUAGUUUUCAGUAAUUACCUGUAGAAGGUGGAGAAGUUACUGGAUAUGUUUAAUAAUAUCUCAUUACAUUCUUUUUUUUUUUUUUUUAACGAGAGUCUUAACUCUGUCACCCAAGCUGGAGUGCAGUGGUGCAAUCUCGGCUCACUGCAAUCUCCACCUCCGGGUUCAAGCGAUUUUCCCGAGUCAUCUUUCCAAGUAACUGGGAUUACAGCUAUGUGCUACCAUGCCCAGCUGAGUUUUGUAUUUUUCUUUCUUUUCUUUCUUUUUUUUUUUUUUUUUUGAGACAGAGCCUCACUCUGUUGCCCAGGCUGGAGUGCCCAGGCUGGAGUGCAGUGGUGUGAUCUCAGCUCACUGCAACCUCCACCUCCUGGGUUCUAGCGAUUCUCCUGCUUCAGCCUCCCGAGUAGCUGGGGUUACAAGCACCCGCCACCACGCCCAGCUAAUUUUUGUGUAUUUAGUAGAGCUGGGUUUUGCCCUGUUGGCCAGGCUGGUCUUGAAUACCUGACCUCAAGUGAUCUGCCCCCCCGACUUCCCAAAAUGCUGGGACUACUGGCAUGAGCCAGUGCUCCUGUCCUCAUUCCAUUCUUCACCGUGGUACUGACCAUCCAUUUAUUCAGCACCAAUUGUGUGCCAGACCUUGUGUCAGCAUUAUGGAGGACUUCCCUUGGGAGGCUUGUUAGCUGUACUUGCAAUCUGAUUUGGGUUCCCAAAUCAGCAUAUAACACCAGGUAUUUCUCUAAUAGAGUAUGUGCCACACUUUCUGCUAACUGCCUGUUUAUCAGUGUCCCCACAUCCCAAUAUCUGGUUCCUUCAAGGGCAGGGAGCACAGGGUAUGGCGUCAGAGUGGUACUCAGUGAUGUUUACUGGUGGGUAGAAGGAAGGGUUAGUCCCUGUUUUUGAAGACUUUAUGUUCUAGCAGGCAGAAAUGAAGCACAAAUAGUUCAAGAAAUAAACAAUUUAGGAAUAAAGUCAUUUGGUUUGCUUCGCAGAAAUGUCUUAUUGCUGAUUUGCCAGCAUGAGUGGCAAAUAUAUAAUAAAACCUGGCCGGGCAUGGUGGCUCACGCCUGUAAUCCCAGCACUUUGGGAGGCCAAGGUGGGCGGAUCACGUGGUCAGGAGAUCAAGACCAUCCUGGCCAACAUGGUGAAAUCCCAUCUCUACUAAAAAUAUAAAAAUUAGCCAGGCAUGGUGGUGGGCGCCUGUAGUCCCAGCUACUUGGGAGGCUGAGGUAGGAGAAUUGCUUGAACCCAGAAGGCGGAGGUUGCAGUGAGCCAAGAUUGCCCCACUGCACUCCAGCCUGGGUGACAGAGUGAGACUCUGUCCCAAAAAAUAAAAAUAAAAAUAAAUGAAUAUAUAAAAUAAAAAAUAUAUGUAUACAUAUCAUAUAUAUAUAUAAAAUAAAACUUAUAAAUAGUUUUUAUGGCUGGGUGAAGUGACUCAUGUCUGUAAUUCUAGCCCUUUGGGAGGCUGAGCGAGGAGGAUCACUUGAGCCUAGGCAUUCGAGCCCAGCCUGGGCAACAUUGCAAGACUCUGUCUCAUUUUUUUAUAUAAAAUGUUUUUUUAAAAAACCCUAUGUAUAAUUAUUUAUUUUUUUUCCCCAAGGAUUAUUCCCAAACUAUGUACAAUUAAUGGGUUGCCUUGCAGAGUUGGAUCAAUAAUACCUGACACACUUGUAUAGCAAGCAUACACUUUACAUAGUUCCUCGCAUCUAUUCUUUGAAACCCAGACACAUUCUAGUAUUGGGCACUAGAAACUGGUGAUAAAUAAUAACAAUUACAUAUAUUUCCUGAAGAAUUAUGUGGCAUUCCUUGUUUUAAGCACCUUUGAUGCCUUAGCUCAAUCUCCAUUACAAUACUAUGAUAUAAGUACCAUUUAAUAUUUCUUUUUGACAGAUGGGAAUAAUCGAGGCCUAGGGAGAUUAAAUUACUUGGCCAGGUUCAUGUAAGUGGCAGAUCUAGGAUUCAAAUUCAGCCGGUCUGAAUCUAGAGCCUAUUCUUUUAGCUAUGAUGCUAUACUUUAAUACAGUAAUACACUGUUCAAAUGAAACUGUAACAUGUCAUUAAAUUUGAACUUGUCAAUAAACAUACCAAGCAAUAAAAUAA